GCCCCGUCCGCGCAGCGCGUCCGGCCCGCCCGCAGGCCAGCUUCUCUCGGGAGCCCCCACCCAGGCGCAUGGCUCCAUGAAGCAAGAGGAGGAGGCAGAGCGCGAGAGGUCCCGUCCGCCCCAGCCGCGUCUGGGCCAGGAGAAAAGGUACAGGAAGAAGGAAUGGAAUCGGAAGGAAGAAAAUUCAUUCCAGAGACAAAAUAGCUCCCCUCCUCUGUUGUAGCUGUUCCUCUGGCAAUACAAACUUUCUGCUUUCAGGUUCUGCAGCAUUCCAGACCUUGAGCACUGAAUCAGGAUGGGAAAAAGACGUUGUGUUCCUCCACUCGAGCCCAAGUUGGCAGCAGGCUGUUGUGGGGUCAAGAAGCCCAAAUUAUCUGGAAGUGGAACGCACAGUCACGGGAAUCAGUCCACAACUGUCCCCGGCUCUAGUUCAGGACCUCUUCAAAACCACCAGCAUGUGGACAGCAGCAGUGGACGGGAGAAUGUGUCAGACUUAACUCUGGGACCUGGAAACUCUCCCAUCACACGAAUGAAUCCCGCAUCGGGAGCGCUGAGCCCUCUUCCCCGGCCUAAUGGAACUGCCAACACCACUAAGAAUCUGGUGGUGACUGCAGAGAUGUGCUGCUACUGCUUCGACGUACUCUACUGUCACCUCUAUGGCUUCCCACAGCCACGACUUCCUAGAUUCACCAAUGACCCCUAUCCGCUCUUUGUGACGUGGAAGACAGGGCGGGACAAGCGGCUUCGUGGCUGCAUUGGGACCUUCUCAGCCAUGAAUCUUCAUUCAGGACUCAGGGAAUACACGUUAACCAGUGCACUUAAGGACAGCCGAUUUCCCCCCCUGACCCGAGAGGAGCUGCCUAAACUUUUCUGCUCUGUCUCCCUCCUUACUAACUUUGAGGAUGCCAGUGAUUACCUGGACUGGGAGGUAGGGGUCCAUGGGAUUCGAAUUGAAUUCAUUAAUGAAAAAGGUGUCAAACGCACAGCCACAUAUUUACCUGAGGUUGCUAAGGAACAAGAUAAUUAUACUGGGGUAACAUCUGACAGGAAGGACGCAGGAGCAGGGAGCCUGGGGACAGCCAUUAUGGCAUGUGUCGGGCUAUCAUCUCAUGUCUCAGAGUCUCCACGGGACUGGCAGACAGACUGGGCGCCAGACUGGGAUCAGAUCCAGACAAUAGACUCCUUGCUCAGGAAAGGUGGCUUUAAAGCUCCAAUUACCAGUGAAUUCAGAAAAACGAUCAAACUCACCAGGUACCGAAGUGAGAAGGUGACAAUCAGUUACGCAGAGUAUAUUGCUUCCCGACAGCACUGUUUCCAGAACGGCACUCUUCAUGCCCCGCCCCUCUACAAUCAUUACUCCUGACACACGGCUGCAUGACCAGUCCCACCCCCCCGUGGCCACCAAUGGCUAUGACAUCAUUGGAGCAGAUGCCUCCUCUUCCUGGUCCAGUUACUUCUAUUACUGCACCAUUUUAUGAUGCUAGCUUCCGUUGCCAAGUCUGCCUCCCGCUGACUGAGGGAGGGUAGGGUUACCUUGAACGAAACAGAACUUGAGGGGCCCAAGCCUUAUCUCAGCCUUUCCUCAAUAUGGGGUUCCGUUGGAUUGGGGCUCCUCCAUGACUAGUGGGAAUUACUGUGGGUUCAGAAGACCCUUGUCUGGUAUUUGCCACAUGGGGUAUUGGCCACACGCUGGAAGCUGAAAUUGAUGAUCCCUGAAGGUUGAACCCACACACACCCCUGCAGCCUCCCCAGAUGAAGUAGGUGUAUUCCCCUGGCAGUCUGGGCAACGGAGACCAAGAAACAUUUUUAGGUUGUUUUAAAUUCCUUUUUUUAAACUUCCAGUUUAUUGCGUACCAAGAGUUGAUUACAACCUCCAUGCUUCAUAAGCGGACGCCACGUUAGGGUUGGACGUGGGCACCACGAGUCCUUUGAGGCUCCUGGACAGAGACCCACAUCAAGAUCGGAAGCCCUUUGGGUGGCGUUGCAGAUCUCAUUGCUCAGUAGGCCGUGAAGAUUUUCAUCCUCAUCCCACUCUCAGUUGGAUUUUCUGGCACUCUUCCUGCAUUGAGUCUCCUGAUUACUGAACAGAGCUCCGUCAUGUAGCCUGCUGAGGAAUGGAAUGGAAUGGAGAUGCCCACAGGAGGUCCUGAUGUCAUCACUGCACGCAGGUGUGAGAGGAGAGACCUCUUCUGCACCGCCUGGCUACCUCACUCCUCUGCUGGUAGCAGUGCCUAUAGCUGGACCUAAGUUCUCAGAAGCGUAGAUGUGCAAACAAGCGAUUGAGUUGGGCUUUAGGAGGACACAUCAUAGGAGAGAAUCCAGGGUCUGUAAGCUGGUUUUCUUUUCAGGUGACAUCCUGAGGGGCCUGUAAGCAGGGGAGCUCCUUUUUCUAGUUUGCCUGUAGAGGUGGGAAGACUGUUGGUGUUUCUGUCCUUUACAGGACAUUAGGAAACAGUUGUGUAAUUACACAAGGUGGACCUUUAUCUUGCCUGACAUGCUGGGAAUCUUCACCCCACCAGGGCAAAUUUCCAAAUAGCUCAUUUUAUUCUAGGUCUUUCAAACUUUCAUGUGACAUAUUUCCCUUUCCCAUUGUUGCUGAUUUCCAAAUCGCUGUCAGCAAUUUUUUCCUCUCUCCUUGCCUAUUCUUCACUCAUUUGGUGGCAAAGUUCAUAGAACUAGGGGACUUGGAAGAUGCUUUGAAAAUAUUGUUACAAAGGCACUGCUAAAAUGAUUCACAGGGAGAGUGGCCAGUUGGAAGAAGGAUCCUAAGGAUGUGACACUGGUUUUCAACAACAUGCUUAGAGAACUCAUGAAGUGGAUUGGGUGUCAACCCAGUGAACAUGUUUUUAUUUAAUUUAUUUUUUGAAGUUUAUGUGGUGAUGGUGUGGCUUUCCGAAAUGGGCAAAUAUUCAGAAGAUCUUUUGCAUUUUCUUCUGUCAGGAAUGGGGAAGGGGAGUGGGGGCACAAUCUGAGAAAGGACACCUGUGCUGUUCUAGGCAUCGCUGGCAAGUUUGUGGGAAGGGAUGGGCAAGGGUGAGUGGGUUUGCUCCACACCGUCCUGUGCUGCUCGAGAGGACCUGGGACGUGCGAGGGAAACGUGGGUGACGGUGCCUAGGCUGCGGCCCUUCACUGCUGUGCUGGGUUCCUGCAGCCUGCUACGUUUCCCUUGGCAAUGUAAAUGAAGAUGGAGGGGUCGUUUCGUGAUUUCCUGCUGCUGAGAAUAAAUGUCUUGUUAAAAACGUGGCAACGGUUACUCUUAGGUGCCAUGGAUCGAUGUCAGGGUGGUCAGCUCUGGACUAAGCCACCCACCUCCAAUUUGUACAACAGUAUUGAUACAUAGGGCUACACUCAUUACUGUUCAAGUGUUCUAUGUUAAGAGUUGUGUUUAAUUUCUAAAGAUUAAAAAAAGCAAAAAAAUUGGUGCUAAACCUUCACCCCUGAGCACGCUCAGUGAGACUGGUCAUGCAAGCAUUUACAGUGCCAUGCUCCUCAAGCCGAUUUUUUCUUGUAGAAAUGUUGCCCUAUUUGUCUUCUCCAAUGUAUGGUAUGUUAUUUUAUUUUAUUAUUUUAUUUUAUUUUAUUUUAUUUUAUCGAGGGGGGGUACGAUACCUGCCAUUUAAGAAAAUGAAUAGAAAAUUUUAAAACCCGAGAAAUGGGGAAAAAAAAAUCAGUGCACAAGAAUUGGGCUGGUUAGGCCCAGCACCACACUGAAGUGGGCUCAGUGGUUUUUGGAGUGAAGAAGCCUUACUCCCUGCACAUUCCCUCAUGCUCCCACACAAGUCCAGCAAUGGAAAUGCUUGGGUUCCUCUUGCUUUGUCAGGGGACUCAGGAGUCGACCAAGGGAAACCAUUUGGCCCCGUGAGGAAUGGGCAUUGUCAGUAUCCGUCCUGAACGGGGCCUAGUCAGGAAGCGGUCUAGAAGUGUACGGUCACGGUCGCCUCAUGAAAGUGUGUAGCAGGUGGCUCUCAGGAAAAAUACCAAGUCUGGAUCAUCCAUGUGGCAGCUUUGCAUAGGGAGAGGAUAGCUCCGAACUGGAACUGAACUGCCUUCUCUGCACGCUUGACCAAAGCAGUGAUGAGGGCGGCCAGUACCUGCGGUGUGCGUGGUAGGUUUAAAGAAAAGGGAAUGUUUUCUGCUGAGUGUUUCCUUUGUCCUUGGGCUGCUCGAGCUGGACAGUAGGUAACCACUGUUUUCAAGGACCAGCCCAAUUUCUCUGGCUUGGUUCGGAGUUCGUUUCAUCCCUAGCUGUGAGUGCCUUUUGGUCUGGAAAGUUGGCUUGUCUCAUAAUACCCACAGCUAGGACAUUCUCUCUGUAAUUAUGAAUUGUCCUUGUUUUACAUUAAAAGAGAAUGUCUUUGAUCACUAGAGUCUGUCGGUGUUGGAUUAUUUCCACUGUGAGAUUCUUAAAACUUUUUUGCUUCAUAAUAAUAAAACAACUCAUGUUAGAGACCCUUUCAACAUGAAAGGUUUGUAGUUGAGACAUUACAUAUAUUUUAUUGUUUAUAAUAAAAAUCAUCUAUACAAAAGAAGUCCUGGGUGUUAAUAUUUUGCACAAGAUCUGUUUUCCAUGAUGUGUUGACAUCUACAAUUUCACUAACUGUUGACGUUAUUUUCUAUUGAGAUUCUGGAGCCUAGGGAGCUAUGUGUUCUUUUUGUUCAUUUCGUUCUUACUUCCCUGAAGCAAGAGACUAUAUGGCCUUCAGUGCAAAGACUUCAGACCAAUUCUUUGUAUUACACUUGGUUGCCUCUUGGCUAUAUAACUUCUGAGUGCAAAUCAUUGAACACUUUAACGAAGUAUUGUAGAGAAUAAAUCAUAAUGGAUAAAAA